ACACCGGCGUGGUACUAGUCACGGAGCCGCACCCCUCGGAAAGCGCGGAGUCGAUGACAGCCACUUCACAGGCUCACGCGCUCCUAGUGUGGGCUUGAAGGGGACGGGGACCGAUUACCAAAGGAGAGCGCUGAGUACGGAAGACACAGGGCAGCCUUUGUCUUGGGUUUAGCGCUGAUGCGCUCAACCCUGAGUCGGGUUCACUGCAACUGUUGUGUCCGAUUUCGGUUCCCUGCAACCGCCCUCCUGGGCGAGAGAUGUCAUUGUGUUCCUGCGGCCAGCGGGACUGAGAGCUGGGACUUAAGACGCCAGGAGGGUCCUGCGCUCACGGGAAAUGUACCCCAAAAGAACUCUGAGAGAAUAUACUCAACUGUCCUGCUGUGAUUAAACAAGACUGCUGUAUUUUACCUGAGCUUGGCAAAGCAAGGAUAUGAACAAUUGUGCAGGUGGGCUACUCAGGGCGAGUGAAGAGAUAAGGCAUCCAAUCAGGGAUUGGCCACCUGCAGCCCUGCCAAUAUGCCCCUCCACCAGAUUUCCGUAAUCCCAGCACGGGAGACUGCCAGCAAUGGGAGAAAUUCAAUGGGCAGAAACAAAGAGAAGAACAAGGAAGUCGAGAAUGAAAAAUCCCCAGGGCGAUCUGCAAGUCGAUCAAGUAACAUUUCAAAAGCAAGCAGCCCAACAACAGGGACAGCUCCCAGGAGCCAGUCAAGGUUGUCUGUCUGUCCAUCCACUCAGGACAUCUGCAGAUCUGCCAUCUUGCAUGACAUGUCAGAAGAGUCAUUUGAGUAUUGCACCCCUGUCAUGGUGCUGAGCCCUGCUAGGAAGGAGUCUGGUAAGAAAUCAGUAAUACAAAGACCUAGGAGGAGGAGAAAAGCCUCUGAGAGAUAUGAGCAUGCUGCAGAAGAACAAAUAAGAGGGAGAAAAAAUGACUUUCACCUUCAAAUCUCAAGCCCCAGGUGGAGGGAGCUUUACACAGAUUCUUCAGAUUCAUCUUCCACAGAUGAGAGUCAUUGGAUUCAGGCAAAAAGAAGAGCCCAGGUUAAAUUCAGACUGUCAAGAAGAAGGAGGAGAAAUAAUAAUAAGCCGUGUGAAAACUUAGCUGGGUCUUCCACUCCUAACGGAAUUGAGCUCGUUGAUCUGGGAUCCAAAGGUAAAGAGCAACAAGAGCUGAUUGAAUGUGAGAGUUGCUCUUUAAAUCUCCACAGAGGAAAACAUACAAGGUACCAAGAAUGCAACCCUUCUCUGACUCAAGGGUCCUCUGAAAUUAAGAGAUCCUCAAGGAAUCAUGAGAAGAGCAAAGGCAGAUAUCACCACAGAGAUCCUCAGCUCUUGCAAAGUCUUAGGAAAAAUGAAAUAAUGAAGAAGACAUUUUCAGAAACAGAUUCCAGCACUGAAAUACUGGGAGUUCCAGAAGGCAGCAAGGACAUGAAUGAUGCAGGGCUCCAGGUGAAUAACCCUGUUCAGAAGCCUCCUGCCACCUAUGACGAUGGGUCUGAUAAUUUAGAAGUAUGCAGAAUCUGUCACUGCGAAGGGGAUGAAGAGAGCCCCCUCAUCACACCCUGUCGCUGCACUGGGACACUGCGCUUUGUCCACCAGUCCUGCCUCCACCAGUGGAUAAAGAGCUCAGAUACACGCUGCUGUGAGCUCUGCAAGUAUGACUUCAUAAUGGAGACCAAGCUCAAACCCCUCCGGAAGUGGGAGAAACUACAGAUGACCACAAGUGAAAGGAGGAAAAUAUUCUGCUCUGUCACAUUCCACGUAAUCGCGAUCACCUGUGUGGUUUGGUCUUUGUAUGUAUUGAUAGACCGGACAGCGGAGGAAAUCAAGCAAGGCAAUGACAAUGGUGUCCUUGAAUGGCCAUUUUGGACAAAACUGGUUGUGGUAGCCAUUGGCUUCACAGGAGGUCUUGUCUUCAUGUACGUACAGUGUAAAGUCUAUGUUCAGUUGUGGCGCAGGCUGAAGGCCUACAACCGUGUGAUCUUUGUACAAAAUUGCCCAGACACUGCCAAAAAACUGGAGAAGAACUUCUCAUGUAAUGUAAACACAGACAUCAAAGAUGCUGUGGUAGUGCCUGUACCACAAACAGGUGCAAAUUCACUGCCAUCUGCAGAGGGUGGCCCCCCUGAAGUUGUAUCAGUCUGAUGGAACCUGUUGGGAGUUUCUUCACCGAAGAAUAUCUUUCUAGCCCUCAGCCACUACAAAUGACAGAAGUGAUCUUGAAUUAUUUACUCCCUUCAGCUCCUCCUUUCUCCUACUGACACAUUUUUCCUGACUUUGUUCAAAGAGGAAAGGAGAAAAACAAACAGACCAAAUGCCCAGGAGCCCAUGAAGUAAUAGCGUAAAGUAAAGUAUGAUAUGGAAAUGUGAAGUUUGCAAGAGAAUGAUUUCCAAGACAAUUAAGAACUACUGGGGCAAUGAAUGCUUUUAGGCAGUAAUCAAAGAUUAAAUGGACCCAUGAUACUCUUCUUCACAGUAACAGGGGAAAAGUUCAAGAAUACAGACUUGAAUUGCGAUGUGUAUUACUUCUAGGGCCUUGUAAUGUUAACUGUCUCAUCUGGAAAUAACUAACAUAUUUGGUUUUAAGCCUGAAAUUGUCUGCAUUAUCCCUAAGUCACAUUGGAAGUGAACUUGGAGGAUGCAUAUUUUGAUAUGCUUUGACAGCUAACAGAUUUGUAUGGUUUAGUGGAGUCUGGUUAUUUUGACAGAUGCAUGUUUUUUUUAAAUAGAUGCAAUAUACAUUUGAAGACAUUGAUAUUUGGAAUUAAUUACGUUUGUUUAAGUCACGCAAAAGAUUUUCAGAAAAUGUUCGGAUAUAAUUAGCUCUGUUAAAUACCCACAGAACUGUUAUCAGGUCUUAUAUUUAUUUUCAUCUGGUUCCUCUAAUACAGUGCUGUCCAAUAGAAACACAACAGCCACAAAUGCAGGCCACAGAUGCAAAUAUUUAACUUCCCAGUAGCCCUAUUUUAAAAAGUAAAAAUAAAUGUUUGUUUGUUAAAAUGAAUUUUGAUUUUUUAAAAACACUAUAUGUUAUUUCAACAUGUCAUCAAUAUAAAAAAUUGAUUGAUUGAUUGAUAGUUUACAUCUGUUUCUUGAACCAAGUUUUCAAAAUCCAGUUGGUAAUUUAAAAGUACACUUCAACUUGAAUUAACUAUAUUGGAUAGCACAGCCGUAAAAUUAGAGACUAAGCUUCUGCUUUAUUUAACAGUUGUUGAGUAUUUCAAAACAGUUUAAUUCAUUCUUUUAUUUCAAAGUCACAAAAGUUAGUUAUGAUUUUUAAAAGCAUUAAAUUAAGUGUCCUCAUUUUAAAGUCAGAUGAAGUUCACAUCUCUAAAGGGUAAAAAUCCAAAAGUAUAGAAAGAUAAAACAAUCAAUCUGCCUAUAGCAGAGUUGUGAAAUAAAUAAAUUGUUACUAUGAAGUACUUACAAUAGGGGAAUAAAAUUACCUAUUUUUGUUAUUAAAUCAAAUGUGUAAGGCUUAUUUCAUCCAUAUGAGGUGUCAACUUGACAGAUGAUGAGUAAUUAUGACUAAGAAUCUAGCCCUUACUUUUAAAAGCUGACAGGAUUUCCCUUGCUCAGUUAGAAAACAAAAAUAUUCAACAGAUUCUGUGAUAAGUAAUUAAUCGUUUAGGUUUGACAGUUGAUUAUUGUGUUCUUUGCAUAUUCAUGUAAAACUGAUGUGUGAAUGACAUUGCAGUGAGCUAGAUUAACGGUGAUUAUAGAUACAGUAGCCUGUCAAAGAAAGAUGUCCUACAUUAAAAAAGGUGACUUAUUUUUGUUAGCUGUCAUUAUUUAUUAACAUGAAAAGGCAAUGAUGGCCAUAAGAACCAAAGCAUGAGUAUCACACUGCACAAAUCUGGGUAUCACAUGGAUGCACUUUGUAAUUAUCAGUGUGCUUGUUCUUCACAGAUCAUAGGAAAAAGGGAAAAAAAAAACAAACCUUUAAAUGAGGAGAAAGAUGGUAUAAAUAUUAGUAGUGGCUGACACUGAGUCCAGAUAGUCUUGAUUCCUAGAAAUAAACAAAAGGUAAACAAUGUCAAUUUUGUGUGUGUGUAUGGCGUGUGUGUAGUCAUGUAUAUAUGCGGGGAAAAUGUUAAGGUAUUCAGUCAGGAAACAAAAGGUUUAAAACUCAUCUUUCUUAAAACUUGUUAUAAGCACAGGGAAAGCAAAGUUGAGGUAACUAAACUGAACCAAAAAUUCUGUAUAAAUAAGGAUAUAAGUAAUUAACGUUUUAAAAAACAUGUGGACCUUAAACAAACUGUAUAUUAAAUUCCUCUUAAAUGCCCAUUUUAAAUAUUUAAGAUAAAUACAUUUAUGAAUAACAAAUCUGUGGGUGAUUUAACCAUGGCACCAUAUCCAAGGGAUUAACCUUAAUGCAAUUUUCCUGUUAAUUGUCCUAAGCUUUUUACUAAUCCAUUUUCCCUGUGGGUUAGUAAUGGCAACAUGCUGCUUACAGAUAUUCCCGGGGAAAAACAUCCAGACACCAGCAAACAAAGAAAUGUUGAUUUCUCUUUUGUUUGCUCUGAAAGUAAAAUAAUUAUUUACUUUAAUUAACAUGGAAAAUAUUGUUUAAAUUCUGUACGAACCUAAACAAGAUACGUUGCAGGGCUGAUUUCACAGUGGAGGAUGAUCGGCUAAAAUAAAGCCUCAUUUAUUAAGGGCUACACUUUUAACACUAAGAAAACAUUUCUAGAAUAAAAAGCAAAGGUAAGCAUUAUUCUAUUAAUAGUAAAAGAGGACAUGGGAUUUUAAAACUAUACCUAAAUUCUUGCAAUUAACUUUUAUGGGCUUGGACAUUGUUGAAAUGAGAAAAUAAUAUAAUAUAGCUUCCUGGCAGGUUAAAAGUCAACACUUGAUUUUGCUAUUCUUCUGACUUUUUGAAACCCUGAAGUUCUGAAUUUCAAGCUUUUAAGAAGCUUUUCAGCAAUGGUUGUUUGUUUAUGGUUCAAACAUCUGAAAUAACUACCUGCAUUUAAAAUCUAAUGUUGAUUAUUUUCUUUUUACAUUCUGUGUGGCAAUGGAACAUUUGCCCUUUCAAACAAUAAAACGAUUUAGCUUUGUGGCAGUGCUUUUUUGUAGACUGACUGACUAUACCCUUCAAAAAGAAAAACUGCUCUACGGAAUGCAAAUUUUGAGGCAUGUUUACCUGCUCGUGGAAGAAAUAAAAUGGAAUUGAAAAAAAAAGGACUAAAAUUGAAGAAUGAAAUUACAGUUGUGUUAAAAACCUUGGCUCUUUAUAAUCAUGAAUCUUCAGUAUUAAACCAGACAUUGAUGCUGUUAAUUUUUUUAAAGAACUAUCACUCUUAUCGUACAGGAGUAAAGAUUAAAUUGUAAAAGAAAGAAAUUCCAAUUUUUUAAAAAGUAAAGCCCAAAAGGCAAUUAAGCUUAAGUACAAAAACAAAAUAAAAAUGAACAAAAUCUAAACUAAAGUGAGCCCAACAACCUGAGAUACAGCAAUGUGUAACCUGAAGGAAGAUAGGUGUAGACUGAAGGAGUCUUUCAAAACACCCCAGCAUUAAAUCUCACUCUGCGCUGCUUCUACACGUGAUUAUAGUCCCAGACAGACGACCUCAUGGUUUUUUAUCUUGUUUUACAAAAGGUCCUUGGGUACUCUUUAAAACAUCUAUUCUUUGGCAGGAAAAUUAGCUCAUUAGAACAAUGACACCAUUAAGGGACAUUAUAAGGGUCCUGGGGCUGAGGUGGGAAGAUUUUUCUAUCUGCCCCAUAUAGUUUACCCUUCCUUGCCUUGAAAAUGAAUAUUAUAGAACAGAGUACAGCUCUUAAAAGUUAUUAGUAUCAUUAUUAUUAUAGUUGUUAUAUAAUACUUUAAUUAAGAAAGAUGAAAACCUUUUUUCUUUCCUAAGUCAGCCCAAUGGUGCUAUUUUACAUAUCAACACAGUUGAAAGGAAGUACUGUUAUUUUGGGCUGCAGUGUUUCCUCCACAUCUAAAGAAAGCCCAUUUUGAAACUGGAUACUGCAUUAAAACAAAGAAGGAAAAAUUAUUUUAACUGUGUGCAGUUUUUGAAAUUAGGCAUUUGUACUAUUUUGGUUUUACAUAAUUCUCUUGCAUUAACAAUUUACUGUUUUGUGAAUCAUGUGUACUAAAGCAAAUUAAGAAAAAGAAAAUAAUUAUCUGUGAAAGACUUUGUAUAUUAAACAAGUGACGCAAACCUUAGUUGUGGUUUCCACAAUUUUUGCCUAACAGACUGAUAUUUGUAUUUGCAACAUCCAAACACACAUACAUUUUUUAAGAUUUUACAAGGGUCUGAACAUAUAAUUAUUUUAAAGCAAACCUACGUUGACUAACUCAUGACAUGGUACAAAUAAAUAAAUACACAAACAGAGGGAAACCAAUGAAAAUAAACUAUGUGGACUUUCAAACCUGCUUUAAAAAAAGAGUUCAAGAGAAAUCACAAUGUAAUCUAAAGCGGGACUGUCUCAAGAAUAAGUCUUGGAUAUAGAAAAAUAAGCAUAUAACAGCAUUUUUCUGUUCAGAGAUAAUAGUGGAUUCAGAUAAUUGCAUGGAUAAUAAACAUUAAAAGCAAGAUAUUAGAAUCUAAGAGGUUUGGUGAUAGCAAAAAACAAAGCUGUUUCC